AAGUUAUUUCCAGGAAGAAGUUUCACCUGUGAUUUCCUCUUCCCCAGAGCCCCACAGUCUUCGUUACAACCUCAUGGUGCUGUCCCAGGAUGGAUCUGUGCAGUCAGGGUUUCUCGCUGAGGGACAUCUGGAUGGUCAGCCCUUCCUGCGCUAUGACAGGCAGAAACGCAGGGCAAAGCCCCAGGGACAGUGGGCAGAAGAUGUCCUGGGAGCUAAGACCUGGGACACAGAGACCGAGGACUUGACAGAGAAUGGGCAAGACCUCAGGAGGACCCUGACUCAUAUCAAGGACCAGAAAGGAGGCUUGCAUUCCCUCCAGGAGAUUAGGGUCUGUGAGAUCCAUGAAGACAGCAGCACCAGGGGCUCCCGGCAUUUCUACUACGAUGGGGAGCUCUUCCUCUCCCAAAACCUGGAGACUCAAGAAUCGACAGUGCCCCAGUCCUCCAGAGCUCAGACCUUGGCUAUGAACGUCACAAAUUUCUGGAAGGAAGAUGCCAUGAAGACCAAGACACACUAUCGCGCUAUGCAGGCAGACUGCCUGCAGAAACUACAGCGAUAUCUGAAAUCCGGGGUGGCCAUCAGGAGAACAGUGCCCCCCAUGGUGAAUGUCACCUGCAGCGAGGUCUCAGAGGGCAACAUCACCGUGACAUGCAGGGCUUCCAGCUUCUAUCCCCGGAAUAUCACACUGACCUGGCGUCAGGAUGGGGUAUCUUUGAGCCACAACACCCAGCAGUGGGGGGAUGUCCUGCCUGAUGGGAAUGGAACCUACCAGACCUGGGUGGCCACCAGGAUUCGCCAAGGAGAGGAGCAGAGGUUCACCUGCUACAUGGAACACAGCGGGAAUCACGGCACUCACCCUGUGCCCUCUGGGAAGGCGCUGGUGCUUCAGAGUCAACGGACAGACUUUCCAUAUGUUUCUGCUGCUAUGCCAUGUUUUGUUAUUAUUAUUAUUCUCUGUGUCCCUUGUUGCAAGAAGAAAACAUCAGCGGCAGAGGGUCCAGAGCUUGUGAGCCUGCAGGUCCUGGAUCAACACCCAGUUGGGACAGGAGACCACAGGGAUGCAGCACAGCUGGGAUUUCAGCCUCUGAUGUCAGCUACUGGGUCCACUGGUUCCACUGAGGGCGCCUAGACUCUACAGCCAGGCGGCCAGGAUUCAACUCCCUGCCUGGAUCUCACCAGCACUUUCCCUCUGUUUCCUGACCUAUGAAACAGAAAAUAACAUCACUUAUUUAUUGUUGUUGGAUGCUGCAAAGUGUUAGUAGGUAUGAGGUGUUUGCUGCUCUGCCACGUAGAGAGCCAGCAAAGGGAUCAUGACCAACUCAACAUUCCAUUGGAGGCUAUAUGAUCAAACAGCAAAUUGUUUAUCAUGAAUGCAGGAUGUGGGCAAACUCACGACUGCUCCUGCCAACAGAAGGUUUGCUGAGGGCAUUCACUCCAUGGUGCUCAUUGGAGUUAUCUACUGGGUCAUCUAGAGCCUAUUGUUUGAGGAAUGCAGUCUUACAAGCCUACUCUGGACCCAGCAGCUGACUCCUUCUUCCACCCCUCUUCUUGCUAUCUCCUAUACCAAUAAAUACGAAGGGCUGUGGAAGAUCAGAGCCCUUGUUCACGAGAAGCAAGAAGCCCCCUGACCCCUUGUUCCAAAUAUACUCUUUUGUCUUUCUCUUUAUUCCCACGUUCGCCCUUUGUUCAGUCCAAUACAGGGUUGUGGGGCCCUUAACAGUGCCAUAUUAAUUGGUAUCAUUAUUUCUGUUGUUUUUGUUUUUGUUUUUGUUUUUGUUUUUGAGACAGAGUCUCACUCUGUCACCCAGGCUGCAGUUCACUGGUGUGAUCUCAGCUCACUGCAACCUCUGCCUCCCAGGUUCAAGCACUUCUCGUACCUCAGACUCCCGAAUAGCUGGGAUUACAGACAGGCACCACCACACCCAGCUAAUUUUUGUAUUUUUUGUAGAGACGGGGUUUCGCCAAGUUGACCAGCCCAGUUUCAAACUCCUGACCUCAGGUGAUCUGCCUGCCUUGGCAUCCCAAAGUGCUGGGAUUACAAGAAUGAGCCACCGUGCCUGGCCUAUUUUAUUAUAUUGUAAUAUAUUUUAUUAUAUUAGCCACCAUGCCUGUCCUAUUUUCUUAUGUUUUAAUAUAUUUUAAUAUAUUACAUGUGCAGUAAUUAGAUUAUCAUGGGUGAACUUUAUGAGUGAGUAUCUUGGUGAUGACUCCUCCUGACCAGCCCAGGACCAGCUUUCUUGUCACCUUGAGGUCCCCUCGCCCCGUCACACCGUUAUGCAUUACUCUGUGUCUACUAUUAUGUGUGCAUAAUUUAUACCGUAAAUGUUUACUCUUUAAAUAGA